CUCUGGACGCUGCGCGGCGCUCCUAGGAGCAGGCGUUCCCGACUCCGGCAAGAGGGUGGCGCCUGGACUCUCGCCCUCAGAGGGAGGCCCGUCCCACGGUCUGUGGCUACGGAUCCCAGGACCCUCUUCGCGGGCGAUUCGCGUAGCCUCAGGUAACUGCAUCCUGCCCAGCAUGACGGCCCCCUGCCCGCCGCCACCUCCAGACCCCCAGUUUGUCCUCCGAGGCACCCAGUCACCGGUGCAUGCGCUGCACUUCUGCGAAGGAGCCCAGGCUCAGGGGCGCCCGCUCCUCUUCUCAGGGUCUCAGAGUGGCCUGGUACACAUCUGGAGCCUGCAGACGCGGAGAGCGGUUACCACCCUGGAUGGCCACGGCGGCCAGUGUGUGACCUGGCUGCAGACGCUGCCCCAGGGGCGCCAGCUCCUCAGUCAGGGCCGGGACCUGAAGCUGUGCCUGUGGGACCUCGCGGAGGGCAGGAGCGCUGUCGUGGACUCCGUGUGCUUGGAGAGUGUGGGCUUCUGCCGGAGCAGCAUCCUGGCCGGGGGCCAGCCACGCUGGACGCUUGCCGUGCCAGGGAGGGGCAGCGACGAGGUUCAGAUUCUGGAGAUGCCCUCCAAGACGUCAGUGUGCGCCCUGAAGCCGAAGGCAGAUGCCAAGCUGGGCAUGCCCAUGUGCCUGCGGCUGUGGCAGGCCGACUGCAGCUCCCGCCCACUCCUUCUGGCCGGCUAUGAGGAUGGAUCGGUGGUCCUGUGGGACGUCUCUGAGCAGAAGGUGUGCAGCCGCAUCGCCUGCCAUGAGGAGCCCGUCAUGGACCUUGACUUUGACUCCCAGAAGGCCAGGGGCAUCUCAGGCUCCGCGGGGAAGGCGCUGGCUGUCUGGAGCCUGGACUGGCAGCAGGCCCUGCAGGUGCGUGGGACUCAUGAACUCACCAAUCCCGGGAUCGCCGAGGUCACGAUCCGGCCAGAUCGCAAGAUCCUGGCCACCGCAGGCUGGGACCACCGCAUCCGCGUGUUCCACUGGCGGACGAUGCAGCCACUGGCCGUGCUGGCCUUCCACAGCGCCGCUGUCCAGUGCGUGGCCUUCACCGCCGAUGGCUUGCUGGCCGCGGGCUCCAAGGAUCAGCGGAUCAGCCUCUGGUCACUCUACCCACGCGCAUGACUCACCCACUCCCUUCCCGGGAGACGAGGAGGGCGGGCAGGGAGGUGGGCAUCAGGCCCCAGCCUUGGCCUGAAACCUCAAGGGCCUCUGAGGACCAGCAAGUCAUGGCCCAAGGACCAUGGAGUCCCCGCUGUCUUCAUGAGGUUGGUAUUUCCUUUUGUGGAGUGCCUCAUCACAGGACGGUGACUCUGGGGGCCAGCCAGAGCCCUGGCCGUCCGAGGCCUGCAGGAGACGUUGGCUUGGGCCUGCUGUGUUGCCAGCUGAGGGUAUUUUAUAAUAAAUUUCCAUUGCCAAGUUGCAGGCUUGAGGUGGGAGCUCCCUGAGGAGGCCCUGGUCCCCCACUUAGCAUCAGUGCCCUCAGACCCCCACCAGGCAGGAUGCUCAGCCCCACCCUCACACCUGCUGUUGAAUGGGCCACCCCGAGUGUGGGUUUCCUGGGCCAGGCCUCAGGAGAUGAUAGGCCCCAACCAUAGCUGCGUCGAUGUCCACAUGACCCCUCACCCCGAGGAGGCCAGGAGCUCCCAACACACAGGUUGAGGCCAGGAUCAGGAUCAGGAAGUAACUGAACUCCCUAAAGAGUGAAGCAGAGAAAGGUGCCUGUGAGGGACGGCAAGGGGGGCUUGCAGCGCACAGGGCCAGGCCAGAUGUGGGAUCCGGGAGGGCACGCCUGCCCGCAGAGGGUGCAGUGGGGAAGGCGCACAGGGUGCACCUCCAGGUGAGUGCUGGGCAGAAGGCACGAGAGCAGCAAGGGAGUGUGACAAGCACCGCCUCACAGUGGCCAAGGCCACAGUCACAGCUGCGGCUGCACACAGGGUGGCCCCCAGGGCACAACACAGCAAGAGCAGGACUUAGCAGCCAGAGCCUCACACUGCAUGCAGCCGGGCCCAGCCUGGCCGGUCGUCUCCUCCUAAAAGCGGGUGUUGAUUGGGAAAGAACCAUGACCCUGAAUAUUGGAGUGGGGCCCAUGGGCAGAUCCAGAGAAGCUGGGACCACACACGCCUGUGUCUGCCCGGAUUGCCGGAAGAGCCCCUCUAGCUGAAGGCCCGGGGUGGCCUCCCUUGAGGCAGUUGCCCUGCAAGGCCCUGCCGAUGCUCCUUGGGACCCCCACCUGGGCUUCUAGUCCUAGAACUAGACUCGAGUCCAGCAGACCCCCAGGAUGAGAUACAGAGGGUGACCCUGAGAGUGGCACCAGCCUCCUGCAGGACCACAUGGCAUUUCCAGGUUUCCAGGCAGAAAUCUGAACAUGUGUGGGACGGAUCGGAAGGGUGUGGGAUCCAGGUGGCCGGAGCAGGGGUGGAUCAGGGGAGUUCCCGGAACAGACCUGCCAAACGGAGGGCUGGACUGGGCGCUGCAGCUUGGGGCCAGGAAGGCUCCAGUGCCGGGCUGGGGGUGGGGGCUGGAUUACAGCCUGAGGGUGGCUGCACUGAGUGAAGUGGACAUGGCCAGCCGCCGUGGGGUACAGCCGAGGAGGGCUUCCAAGGCCUGGGGAUGGGGGUGUUGGAUUUGUCAGUGAGACCUGUGCACCCACUGCAGGGGGUCCCAAGGCCGUGCCUCCCCAACCCCACUGUGAGGAACAUGGUUGCUGGGGGGCCCGGAGUCCUUGAGGAGUCCUGUGACCACACUUCUCUGUUGGUCAGAGGUACCAUGGGGACCGUUCCAUCAAACGGGAAUGUCAGUGCUGGCCGGGAAAGCGGCCCCUGGCCCAAGCUUGGAGACCACCUGGCUCGGGUACUGGCCUGGCUCCGUUGGACAAGGGUGGCCACCAGGUGCCCAGGACCUUUGGAGAGGGGGGCCCUGCUGCUUUUCCUCGAGUGUCCUAUAGCCGCCAGGAUGCGUAGGGCACUCCGGGAGGUAUUUUCAUAUCACUGAGGUGUCAGGGAGGGGAAGGGUCCUGGGUUUAGGCUGCAGUGACUGCAGGUGCUGAGGGAGCUGUGCCCUGGGUGCUCAUCACAGGCUGUCACAGUGAGGGAAGGUGUCAGGUUCUGACAUCCCCAUGACAGCGGCAGGGUAGGUGGAGUGGGAAUUGGCUUUGCAGUUUCCCUGCAUGCCCUUGACAGCCUUGCCAAAGGCACAUCUGCCCCGCCUCAGCUCCCACCCUGAGGGUUCUGGGCCUCUACCCCUUCCCCUGUUUAUGUCCCUGUCAUCUUUGGCAUCAUCACUGUAGUUACAAAACUCCCUACGUCCCACAGCCACGAGGUGGGUAUCCCACAUGAGGGCCCAGGUGUGCAUGCCAGCAUGAGGUUGGCGAGUGGCACUGCCUGCUGAUGUCUUACAUAGAGGCCAUGAAGAGCUGUGGGCAGGGUGUACAGACCCUGAGUUGGCCCCUGGCCCUCGUGCUUUCAGUCAAAGGCACAAGCAGGGUGGAUGGCAGGCGGCUGCCCCCUAGCCUGGCCUUGAGCUCCCUGCCCCAGGCCAUGUGGCGUUGAGCAGUGUCCAGGCACAUCUUGUUCUGAAUCUCAGUGUGCAGGGAUGGAGUCGGGACAGCGUGAGUCCUGCAUGCCUAACACAGCCCUCACCCCUCCAGUGCACAACGGGGCCACGUGCCCGCAUCUGGGUGGCUAGGCAGAUAGGGCCCCCCUUGCCAGGCAGAUCCAGCUUCUGAGGCCUUAUAGACGUCCUGUGGAGGGCAGGCCCAGGACUUUCAUUCACCUGGCUGAGCUGCCUGGGAGAGCAGCAGAACCGGUGCUGGGGUCCAAGCCGGCCAAGAGCAGUGCAGCCCUCCUGGUCCUGUUCCUCUCUUGAGCUGCUCCGUGGUGUCCACAGCAGAGCCAUGUGGCUCUGGACAGGUCGGCCUUUGUGUCAACAGAACCUGGGUCGUGAUGAAUCACCAUGCGUCUGACCAGCCUUGAAACCCCCACAACAGAAGAAGAAACGGUCUCAGCUCCAGACAUCCAGCUUGGAAAAGAUGCACCUGAACAUUGGCAUUCUCUUCCUAGCAAACAGCCACUUCCUGUAGGCUGGCAGGAACGCCAACAGAGCCAGCAGUGAAGGCAUUAAGUGGGGAGGAGGGGUGGCCCGGAGGCAGCACGCGAAGGUCAGCAUGCAGCUCCUGGGAUGAACCUGAGAGGCGACUCCUGGCAGCAUGGCUGGUCGCUGCCAUCACGCCCCUGGCCAACCCACCAACUGGGAGAGGCAGCCCUUCCACAUCUUCCUCCAUAAUGCUCUUGGGUAGCAGUGAGGCCUCUCAAGCCAGAGAGAACUUGGUGUUUGGAAACAACGGCGGACAUUUCUUGCCAUUUUCAGUGCCAACUCAGGUAGGUGUGUUCUACCAUCCUGUGUUUUUGGGGUGUUUUUUUUUUUGAGUCAGAGUCUCACUCUGUCCCCCAGGCUGGAGUGCAAUGGAGCAGUCUCGGCUCACUGCAACCUCUGAUUCCCAGGUUCAAGCGAUUCUCCUGCCUCAGCCUCCCGAGAAGCUCAGGACCACCCACAUAGGUGCAGGCCAUCAUGCCCAGCUAAUUUUUUAUUUUUUUUUAUAGAGAAGGAGUCUCGCUAUGUUGCCCAGGCUGGUUUCGAACUCCUGGGCUCAAGCGAUCGAUCCUCCCGCCUCUAGCCUCCCAAAGCACUAGAAUUAUAGGCCUGAGCCACUGCGCCCGGCCCACCAUCCUGUUCUUAUUGGAAGAAUUUCCAUGUGUCGAGGCACGGGCACAACGUAGCUGGUCCUCUGCUCAGGGCCCCACAAGGCUGCGUCAGGGUGGCAGCGCGGCUGGGGGCUUUUUCUGUUCAAAUCCAGAUUCUCGUGGCUGUGAGCCCCAGCCCUGGGCACUGUCCGCCUGGUGGUGUCUUCACAGCCAGCAGGGGUGGCCUUGGGGUGUUCUGUGGAGUAACUUUCACGGCCCAGAGUGGGAUCCUGAGUGGCUGGAGCCGUAUGCUCCAGCAUCCCCAGCCGCUGCCUCCGGUGCAGGUGGAGUGGGCCCCUCUGAUUACCAGGAGCUGUCAGAGGGGCAGCAGGUCCCACUCCACUGGCCGGUGGGCAGCUGUGUGCAGGGACGCGGGUCCUGGCACGUCUGCCUGGUGAGGCCCUGCCUCCAGUGCCAAGGGGCCUCCCCUCUCGACGGUGGGCGCCACCAUGUGCUGACCUCUGUGCAGCCCCACUUUACAAGGUAGGUUCGGCCAGCACCCCAUCCGCGGGCGGGCAGCACUCACCCAGCGUUGCGCCGCCAACAGGGUCCCUCUUAGACAAGCAGCUGUGCCUAGAGCCUUUUCCUUCCUCCCUGCGUGUUACCUGCAGGCCAACAGACGGCCCUGGGUCUGGGACCAGGAGAACCUGCCUCCGCCUCUGGCAGUGGGUGUCCCUGCAGGCAGAUUGGGCUUGGCACGUAGACACCGAGGGGUCAGCCGAUGCCGGGAGAUGAUCCCGGGAAGGGCUCCGGAGCACAGCCCAGGACCCGCCGCCGCUGCUGGGCGCUCCAUGUUGACGUGCUGUGCGUGUCUCCACUCCCCAGGCAAUGAUGUUCAAUCAGGUGUUUCCCACCUGUGUCUCUGCCAAGAAGCCACAGAACACCCUCUGCACAAAAGGAGUGUUUGCACAAAGAAAAACAACCCUCCGGGGGUUCUUUAGAAAUGCUUAUACUCAAUUAGCUAGAACUUCAUGUGAAAUCCCAGCGUGGAAGACAACAAGCCGGCACCGGUGAAAACUUUGCUGUGCACCUGCCCUCUACCAAGCUGCCAGCCCCACCAGCCCUGUGGUCCUAGGUGGGCACAGCUGCUGCACGGUCCCCCAGGCCUGCCUCUCCUCGGGGUCUCAACCUUCAUACCAGAUUUGCCAGCAUCCCCAUUCCCGCCUUGUGGGUGGAGAGUCCUUGAGACCCUCUGUCACUCUGUCAGCUUCCCCAGGUCAGCGAGCUGUGGCUUGGCUCCCACGCAUCAGCUUUUAUGGGAGGCCCAUUAGGAGCUGGGCAGGAGGGACAGAGGGGAGGCCAGGCAGCCACUGCUGAGUGGGACGGGUAGCCCAGCCCAUGAGGCUGGCCAGCCCUACAGGGGAGGUCCCACAGCACUGGCCGGGAAGUCCACAUAGGAAAGCAUCAGUUGAGGGAUGAAGCCACGGACGAUGGGGACAACGGCCACAGGGUGUGCUAAGCUGAGGAAAUUAGUAGGAGGUGCUCAUAAGCUGUUUUGUUUUUUGGUUUGUUUGUUUGUUUUUUCUUUUAAGAGACCAGGGACAGUGGGGGUCUCACUCUGUCACCCAGGCUGGAGUGCAGUGGCAUGAUCAUAGCUUACUGCAGCCUCCAACUAAUAGGCUCAAGUGAUCCUCCUGCCUCAGCCUCCCGAGUAACUCAUGGCCUUUAAGUGAACUGCUUCCACCAUCCAGCUGUGCAGGUGGCCUGGGAACAGCAGCACAUCUGUCCCCUGCCACCUCUUGCAUGCACACUUGACCUCCUGACUUGGGCUCUGAAACCUGUAAAAUGUGGGGUGUAGAGAAAUCGAGUCAUUUGGCCUCAUCCUGGUGCCAUUAUCUCUUGCUACAUUAAUAAACCACCUCAAACAGA